UUGCAUGUCCACCCGAACGCUUCGCACUUCUUUGCCCUUGUCCUCGCAGCCUUAAAUCUGCGACCUUCCCUGGGGGCACAGUCUGGUCCUACUUGAUUGAUAGUUCUGUGUUUUGAGAGGUUUUAAAGCUCUUCAGCUCGGGACCUCGGCGCCCACACCACGCGCCCAGCUCCCUCACCCUCUGUCGGCAACGCGGCCACCACUGCUCACUGCCCCUCCUGCAUGGCCCCUGCCAACGCUAAUACCAGAGUUAGGCCGAUUGGAAAUGGAAGCUUUGUUUCACCUAAAUGUUUAUUUAGCAAAGAGUUCGUCCCCAACGUUAGUCGUAAUUGUGGAGUCGGUGUAAUUAGUUAUUAGCUUCUUUCUCUGCCUCUUCUCUGCCUUCCGCCGCGUGCCCAGAGCCCCAUUCGCAUUUCAUCGGAGAUGGACGUGCCACCUUCAGCUUCCACAGGGGAAGAGGCCCUGCCACAGUCAUUUAAAUGGAUUGUGUAGGGAUUCCUGACACAGCUAGCGAUUCAUUGAGGUGGCAAGAUAAACUGGCGGAAUGAGGCCUUUAUCAAAGGCCUUUAUCAAAGAGGAGUCUGCUAUCAACUUAGUAACAAAUUUGGGGAUCCUGAUCUGGAAUUGGAAGAUCCACGUCACCCUCCUUCAUGGACCUGGAGCUCCCCACUUCCACACCACCACCAGCGGGCACAUGCGGCAGAUGUUGACAUCUUGCUGGAGUUGCAACACUCAAGAAGAAACAAAAAGAAAAGACCUCCUCUGGCGUGGUCACCGGCCAGUGAUGAUGACAGCCUCUUCAUCUAUGACUGCAGUGCUGCAGAAAAGAAGUCACAAGAAAAUAAAGGGGAGGACGCGCCCUUGGACCAGGGGAGCGGUGCGAUUCUGGCGUCCACCUUCUCCAAGUCUGGCAGCUAUUUUGCUUUAACCGAUGACAGUAAGCGUCUGAUUCUUUUCCGUACAAAACCAUGGCAAUGUCUGAGUGUCAGGACCGUGGCAAGGAGGUGUACAGCCCUGACUUUCAUAGCCUCGGAGGAGAAGGUCUUGGUGGCCGACAAGUCUGGAGACGUCUACUCCUUUUCGGUGCUGGAGCCACACGGGUGUGGCCGUCUAGAGCUGGGGCACCUGUCUAUGCUGUUAGAUGUGGCUGUGAGUCCUGAUGACCGCUUCAUCCUCACUGCCGACCGGGACGAGAAGAUCCGAGUCAGCUGGGCCGCGGCGCCCCAUAGCAUCGAGUCCUUCUGCUUGGGGCACACAGAGUUUGUGAGCCGUAUCUCCGUGGUGCCAACUCAGCCCGGGCUGCUUCUGUCCUCCUCUGGGGACGGCACCCUGAGGCUCUGGGAGUACAGGAGCGGCCGCCAGCUGCACUGCUGUCACCUGGCCAGUCUGCAGGAGCUGGUGGACCCCCAGGCCCCCCAGAAGUUUGCCGCGUCCAGGAUUGCAUUCUGGUGCCAGGAGAACUGCGUGGCGCUCCUGUGCGACGGCACUCCUGUGGUCUACAUCUUCCAGCUGGACGCCCGCAGACAGCAGUUGGUGUACAGGCAGCAGCUGGCGUUCCAGCACCAAGUGUGGGACGUGGCUUUCGAGGAGACCCAGGGGCUGUGGGUGCUCCAGGACUGCCAGGAAGCCCCCCUGGUGCUCUACAGGCCUGUGGGCGACCAGUGGCAGUCUGUUCCUGAGAGCACCGUGUUAAAGAAAGUCUCUGGUGUUCUUCGUGGGAACUGGGCCAUGCUGGAAGGCUCUGCCGGCGCAGACGCCAGCUUCAGCAGUCUCUACAAGGCCACGUUCGACAACGUGACCUCCUACCUGAAGAAGAAAGAGGAGAGACUGCAGCAGCAGCUAGAGAAGAAGCAGCGGCGCCGGAGUCCCCCGCCUGGGCCCGACGGGCAUGCCAAGAAGAUGAGACCGGGGGAGGCGACGCUAAGUUGCUGAUCGUGGCGGUCAGUGGUGUCUCUCACCUCAAAUUAGGAAAAGCUUUUUAACUUGUUCCCCUGCAUCCUGGCAUGUCCCUUCAAGAAGGAAAAGGUGACAUCAGUUGUGACCAGCUCAGAGGAUGGGGCUGUCCCCUGGGCUCUAGAAAGAACAUUCUGUGUCACCAGCACAGGCUCUUGCUGGGUGCCUGUGCCCCCUUUCUGGUUGAAGGGAAGCCAGACCAGUGGAGUGGAAGCUCUUGAAGCACUUUCUUUUCAUGUCGGAGGCUGCGUGUGAGCCGGUGGUGGCGGCAGCUGUCUGUGUUUCUCCUGUUCUCAUACCGCCCUUCGUGUCCGCUGCAUCUUCCUCUAGGAGCAUCUGUGGGCUGACGUUUCUGGCAUGGUGGAUGUUUUCAUGUUGUUCCGCCGUCUCAGCAUCCAGGUGACGUGCUGUCCCGCAGUAGCUGCUCGCCACACAGGCUGUUGAAACUCAGCACGAAUGCUUGAGCCUGCCCCAGCCCCAGCCGUAGCCCUUGUGCUCAGGAGCUGCUCCUGGAGAGUGGCUCCCUUGUGGGAAGUGAGAAACACGUUUCGGAGUCGCAGGGAGCUCUGUCUGGCAUCGGUGGCACAGAUGGUGAACUUGUUUCAGGAAGUGUGAGCACGGGCCUGGCUGGCACCCGGUUUACAGGGAGGUGAUUGAGGACGUCGUUAUGAUUUGAUUUGACCUUGGCACACACUGCAGAGCCACAGGGAUGUUGCUGAAUUUCAAUCACCGAUCAGCAAGGAUGAACCUUCUCAACUUCCUAGGAAUGUUUAGCAGCAACCGAAUAUACCAGGCAAAACUC